CACCCAGAGGCUGAUGCUCACCAUGGGGCGCCUGCAACUGGUUGUGUUGGGCCUCACCUGCUGCUGGGCAGUGGCGAGUGCCGCGAAGCUGGGCGCCGUGUACACAGAAGGUGGGUUCGUGGAAGGCGUCAAUAAGAAGCUCGGCCUCCUGGGUGACUCUGUGGACAUCUUCAAGGGCAUCCCCUUCGCAGCUCCCACCAAGGCCCUGGAAAAUCCUCAGCCACAUCCUGGCUGGCAAGGGACCCUGAAGGCCAAGAACUUCAAGAAGAGAUGCCUGCAGGCCACCAUCACCCAGGACAGCACCUACGGGGAUGAAGACUGCCUGUACCUCAACAUUUGGGUGCCCCAGGGCAGGAAGCAAGUCUCCCGGGACCUGCCCGUUAUGAUCUGGAUCUAUGGAGGCGCCUUCCUCAUGGGGUCCGGCCAUGGGGCCAACUUCCUCAACAACUACCUGUAUGACGGCGAGGAGAUCGCCACACGCGGAAACGUCAUCGUGGUCACCUUCAACUACCGUGUCGGCCCCCUUGGGUUCCUCAGCACUGGGGACGCCAAUCUGCCAGGUAACUAUGGCCUUCGGGAUCAGCACAUGGCCAUUGCUUGGGUGAAGAGGAAUAUCGCGGCCUUCGGGGGGGACCCCAACAACAUCACGCUCUUCGGGGAGUCUGCUGGAGGUGCCAGCGUCUCUCUGCAGACCCUCUCCCCCUACAACAAGGGCCUCAUCCGGCGAGCCAUCAGCCAGAGCGGCGUGGCCCUGAGUCCCUGGGUCAUCCAGAAAAACCCACUCUUCUGGGCCAAAAAGGUGGCUGAGAAGGUGGGUUGCCCUGUGGGUGAUGCCGCCAGGAUGGCCCAGUGUCUGAAGGUUACUGAUCCCCGAGCCCUGACGCUGGCCUAUAAGGUGCCGCUGGCAGGCCUGGAGUACCCCAUGCUGCACUAUGUGGGCUUCGUCCCUGUCAUUGAUGGAGACUUCAUCCCCGCUGACCCGAUCAACCUGUACGCCAACGCCGCCGACAUCGACUAUAUAGCAGGCACCAACAACAUGGACGGCCACAUCUUCGCCAGCAUCGACAUGCCUGCCAUCAACAAGGGCAACAAGAAAGUCACGGAGGAGGACUUCUACAAGCUGGUCAGUGAGUUCACAAUCACCAAGGGGCUCAGAGGCGCCAAGACGACCUUUGAUGUCUACACCGAGUCCUGGGCCCAGGACCCAUCCCAGGAGAAUAAGAAGAAGACUGUGGUGGACUUUGAGACCGAUGUCCUCUUCCUGGUGCCCACCGAGAUUGCCCUAGCCCAGCACAGAGCCAAUGCCAAGAGUGCCAAGACCUACGCCUACCUGUUUUCCCAUCCCUCUCGGAUGCCCGUCUACCCCAAAUGGGUGGGGGCCGACCAUGCAGAUGACAUUCAGUACGUUUUCGGGAAGCCCUUCGCCACCCCCACGGGCUACCGGCCCCAAGACAGGACAGUCUCUAAGGCCAUGAUCGCCUACUGGACCAACUUUGCCAAAACAGGGGACCCCAACAUGGGCGACUCGGCUGUGCCCACACACUGGGAACCCUACACUACGGAAAACAGCGGCUACCUGGAGAUCACCAAGAAGAUGGGCAGCAGCUCCAUGAAGCGGAGCCUGAGAACCAACUUCCUGCGCUACUGGACCCUCACCUAUCUGGCGCUGCCCACAGUGACCGACCAGGAGGCCACCCCUGUGCCCCCCACAGGGGACUCCGAGGCCACUCCCGUGCCCCCCACGGGUGACUCCGAGACCGCCCCCGUGCCGCCCACGGGUGACUCCGGGGCCCCCCCCGUGCCGCCCACGGGUGACUCCGGGGCCCCCCCCGUGCCGCCCACGGGUGACUCCGGGGCCCCCCCCGUGCCGCCCACGGGUGACUCCGGGGCCCCCCCCGUGCCGCCCACGGGUGACUCCGGGGCCCCCCCCGUGCCGCCCACGGGUGACUCCGGGGCCCCCCCCGUGCCGCCCACGGGUGACUCCGGGGCCCCCCCCGUGCCGCCCACGGGUGACUCCGGCGCCCCCCCCGUGCCGCCCACGGGUGACGCCGGGCCCCCCCCCGUGCCGCCCACGGGUGACUCCGGCGCCCCCCCCGUGCCGCCCACGGGUGACUCCGGGGCCCCCCCCGUGACCCCCACGGGUGACUCCGAGACCGCCCCCGUGCCGCCCACGGGUGACUCCGGGGCCCCCCCUGUGCCCCCCACGGGUGACUCUGAGGCUGCCCCUGUGCCCCCCACAGAUGACUCCAAGGAAGCUCAGAUGCCUGCAGUCAUUAGGUUUUAGCGUCCCAUGAGCCUUGGUAUCAAGAGGCCACAAGAGUGGGACCCCAGGGGCUCCCCUCCCAUCUUGAGCUCUUCCUGAAUAAAGCCUCAUACCCCUG